CCCCUCCCCCCUGGGUCGGACGCUGAGCGGAGCCGCGGGCGGGAGGGCGGACGGACCGACUGACGGUAGGGACGGGAGGCGAGCAAGAUGGCGCAGACGCAGGGCACCCGGAGGAAAGUCUGUUACUACUACGACGGGGAUGUUGGAAAUUACUAUUAUGGACAAGGCCACCCAAUGAAGCCUCACCGAAUCCGCAUGACUCAUAAUUUGCUGCUCAACUAUGGUCUCUACCGAAAAAUGGAAAUCUAUCGCCCUCACAAAGCCAAUGCUGAGGAGAUGACCAAGUACCACAGCGAUGACUACAUUAAAUUCUUGCGCUCCAUCCGUCCAGAUAACAUGUCGGAGUACAGCAAGCAGAUGCAGAGAUUCAACGUUGGUGAGGACUGUCCAGUAUUCGAUGGCCUGUUUGAGUUCUGUCAGUUGUCUACUGGUGGUUCUGUGGCAAGUGCUGUGAAACUUAAUAAGCAGCAGACGGACAUCGCUGUGAAUUGGGCUGGGGGCCUGCACCAUGCAAAGAAGUCCGAGGCAUCUGGCUUCUGUUACGUCAAUGAUAUCGUCUUGGCCAUCCUGGAACUGCUAAAGUAUCACCAGAGGGUGCUGUACAUUGACAUUGAUAUUCACCAUGGUGACGGCGUGGAAGAGGCCUUCUACACCACGGACCGGGUCAUGACUGUGUCCUUUCAUAAGUAUGGAGAGUACUUCCCAGGAACUGGGGACCUACGGGAUAUCGGGGCUGGCAAAGGCAAGUAUUAUGCUGUUAACUACCCGCUCCGAGACGGGAUUGAUGACGAGUCCUAUGAGGCCAUUUUCAAGCCGGUCAUGUCCAAAGUAAUGGAGAUGUUCCAGCCUAGUGCGGUGGUCUUACAGUGUGGCUCAGACUCCCUAUCUGGGGAUCGGUUAGGUUGCUUCAAUCUAACUAUCAAAGGACACGCCAAGUGUGUGGAAUUUGUCAAGAGCUUUAACCUGCCUAUGCUGAUGCUGGGAGGCGGUGGUUACACCAUUCGUAACGUUGCCCGGUGCUGGACAUAUGAGACAGCUGUGGCCCUGGAUACGGAGAUCCCUAAUGAGCUUCCAUACAAUGACUACUUUGAAUACUUUGGACCAGAUUUCAAGCUCCACAUCAGUCCUUCCAAUAUGACUAACCAGAACACGAAUGAGUACCUGGAGAAGAUCAAACAGCGACUGUUUGAGAACCUUAGAAUGCUGCCGCACGCACCUGGGGUCCAAAUGCAGGCGAUUCCUGAGGACGCCAUCCCUGAGGAGAGUGGCGAUGAGGACGAAGACGACCCUGACAAGCGCAUCUCGAUCUGCUCCUCUGACAAACGAAUUGCCUGUGAGGAAGAGUUCUCCGAUUCUGAAGAGGAGGGAGAGGGGGGCCGCAAGAACUCUUCCAACUUCAAAAAAGCCAAGAGAGUCAAAACAGAGGAUGAAAAAGAGAAAGACCCAGAGGAGAAGAAAGAAGUCACCGAAGAGGAGAAAACCAAGGAGGAGAAGCCAGAAGCCAAAGGGGUCAAGGAGGAGGUCAAGUUGGCCUGAAUGGACCUCUCCAGCUCUGGCUUCCUGCUGAGUCCCUCACGUUUCUUCCCCAACCCCUCAGAUUUUAUAUUUUCUAUUUCUCUGUGUAUUUAUAUAAAAAUUUAUUAAAUAUAAAUAUCCCCAGGGACAGAAACCAAGGCCCCGAGCUCAGGGCAGCUGUGCUGGGUGAGCUCUUCCAGGAGCCACCUUGCCACCCAUUCUUCCCGUUCUUAACUUUGAACCAUAAAGGGUGCCAGGUCUGGGUGAAAGGGAUACUUUUAUGCAACCAUAAGACAAACUCCUGAAAUGCCAAGUGCCUGCUUAGUAGCUUUGGAAAGGUGCCCUUAUUGAACAUUCUAGAAGGGGUGGCUGGGUCUUCAAGGAUCUCCUGUUUUUUUCAGGCUCCUAAAGUAACAUCAGCCAUUUUUAGAUUGGUUCUGUUUUCGUACCUUCCCACUGGCCUCAAGUGAGCCAAGAAACACUGCCUGCCCUCUGUCUGUCUUCUCCUAAUUCUGCAGGUGGAGGUUGCUAGUCUAGUUUCCUUUUUGAGAUACUAUUUUCAUUUUUGUGAGCCUCUUUGUAAUAAAAUGGUACAUUUCUAUA